CUAUCUCCACAUUUAAGGAGCUUAUGAUCUGAUUGAAGUGAACAUACCUUCAGAAAAUAAGAUAGAUCUGAUAGAAAGUAGCAGGCUGAGAUUGAGGCUCCAGAUUUGGUAAUUGUGUGAAAACAAGAAUGAAUCAAGUAUCCCAAGUUGCAUGGAAAAGUAGUGGGUUUGUAUUAGAGGCCUGGGACAUUUUUGAGACAGUUUUGCUCUUAUUACCCAGGCUGGAGUGCAGUGGCCGAUCUUGGCUCACUGCAACCUCCGCCCCCUGGGUACAAGCGAUUUUUCUUUUCUGCCUCAGCUUCCCAAGUAGCUGGGACUACAGGCAUGUGGCACCACGCCCAGCUAAUUUUUGUAUUUUUGGUAGAUACGGGGUUUCACCAUGUUGGCCAGGCUGGUCUCAAUCUCCUGACCUUGUGAUCUACCUGCCGCGGCCUCCCAAAGUGCUGGGAUUACAGGUGUGAACCACCGCGCGAGGCCUGGUACUUUUCUAGUGACGAAGUGUUGAAACCGCUGGUGGUCACAUUGAAAAGCAUUCAGAGAUACUAGAUCACAUUACAUCUUAAUUGCAGAUAGUUCCAGCUUUCAAAUCAGAUUUUUGGUAGGAGCUUAGCACAUAUCUUUCUGUGGGAACUGUGUUAUAAUGAGGGCUAGUACGUUCUCAAGUAGUACACACAAGGCCAUUUAAUGCAUCGUAUCCUUGAAGUAUGUGUUACACUAUUAGGCUAAACUGUAAGAAAUUACUGUUUUUGGAAGUCACAGAUCACCAGAUGUUGGCAGUUUCACAUGGUUCAAUCCGGUACAUUUAAUUAUCACCAGACAUUUUUUUUUAGCUUAGUGAAUUUUUAAAAUUUAUUAUCAUUUAUGUACUUUUUAUUUCAAUACUUUUAGGGUACAAGUAGUUUUUGGUAUCACCAGACAUUUGAUGUCUAUAAUUUAUUUGGGAAGACACUGAGACUGCAGAAUUGACCUGAUAGCUGUGUUUUAAAAGCAUUUCUCUGAGACCAUUCAGGGUUUUAAAUUGGGAUGUCUGAGACUGAAGGCCCUUCUGCCCCAGGGAUUCUCCUUAAUCCCAAGUUUCUGAUGGGUUUUCUCUCUAUAGUCAUCCUCCUUCCCCUGAUCCCCAAAAUAAGACUAGGGAGGUGGGAGUAUUUUAGGGUGGUGUUUCUCUUUUCUGUUUUUGAGAUGGGGUCUUACUCUGUUGCCCAGGCAGGAGUGCAGUGGCAGGAUCUCAGCUCACUGCAACCUCUGCCUCUCAGGUUCAAGUGAUUCUCCUGCCUCAGCCUCCCGAGUAGCUGGGACUACAGGUGCUUGCCACCAUGCCCAGCUAAUUUUAGUAUUUUUUAGUAGAAACAGGGUUUUACCAUGUUGGCCAGGCUGGUCUCAAACUCCUGACCUCAAGUGAUCUGCCCGCCUUGGCCUCCCAAAGUGCUGGGAUUACAGGCGUGACCCACCGUGAUUGGCAAGGGUGGUGUUUUGCUAACUGUAGGUUAGUUUUUCUAACUGUAGGUUUUUAACAGGAUUUAUCACAAAUGAAAGACAAUAGAAAAUAUUCAGGAAACAUUGCACAUGGUAAUGGCAAGUGUUUCAUGAAACAUUUAGUGUCUGUGCAUUUGUGUGUGUGUGUGUGUGUACUGGGUUGUAUAUGCAGUGUAUUUAUUUAUCACAGGCCUUAAACAUUUGAGUAAUGCUGAUUUGGGAGAUGAAUUGAUGUAGGCUUGGCAUCUUGGGGAUAGAAGGUAAGCCAUUGUAGGGGUCCUCGGACUUCUUUAACCUUUUGCCCUCCUAUUGUGGGCCAGAAAGUAGGCCUUCUCUCUCUCCACUGGUGCCAUCAAACUCCUCUGAACUCUGGCUCAUGUCUUUCCUUUACCUGCAUGUAACGCAAUGUAAUUUAGUAUAGAGUAGAAUCCUUUGGAAUUUUUUUAAAGGUGAUUCCUGGUAGUUGCUGGUAUAAAGGUGGUUAAAAACAGAAAACCUAAAGCACAGAGAUAGUGUUCUCAUUUAAGUGUUUUAAGUAGAACAUGAAACUUUCUAAGUUGAGUUUUUGUAGAGUGAUCACUGAGAAUUCAUCUAUAUUUCAGAGGAAAACAAGAAAGACUGGUAGGUAGGCACUUGAUAGAUUUGUGGAAUGGGUGGAGACAGUUCUGAGCACCUGUCUAGGAUCAGUGAACUACGUAUUAGUGAAUAUGAAGCAGAAGUUGAUAGUAGGAACAGAGAGGUGAUUAUCUUCCCCUUUUUUUCUGUGCUGUACUAUCUUGGAGAGGUGAGGAGAAAAAGGUUCCAAAUUGGCCACUAGAUGAUUGAAAGAAGUCCCUGUGGCCAAUUUUGUAUCUGGAUGACCAUUCUUUUUUAAGUGAGAUGCGUGAACCUUUCAUAUAAAGAGCUGCUGGCAGGAUAUUGUUUUAUUAGGUUUUAGGGAUAUUGGCCCAUGGUUCACUUUUUCUUUCUCCCCAGUUUUUGGAAAAGUUGAUUGCUAGUAAGGCUGAUUGCUUUCAGGGAAUUGUCAUUUUCCUCCGGGGGAUGUUUGGAUGAGAAUGGAGACCAGUUUGGCAAGGGCAACAGCUGUUGAACAAUCUGUUUGGGAUUAGGUGCAAGUUGGUAUGUAGUGGAAAUCUGCCUCCUGGUUCCUGAAAUUAUGUUCCUUUGCCUCAAGGAUAAAUGUUUUCCUGCUCAUUCCAGUUACAUUCACUUAGUUCUGGCUGGUAAUGCUUCUGACUGAUAACUUUCCUCUUUUAAGAGAGCUUCCUUGAAAGAAUAAUUGAUAGCUACGAUGAACAAUUAAAAAUGUUAUGCCUUCCCUUAAGAUUUUGCUCAGGAUUUAAUCAUAGGUUGGUGGUAACAGAACCUUUCAGUUCAAAAUUAGCUGUAUAUUAUCUAACCAUUUUGGUAAGGGGAGAGACUUAAGGUGCUUUCUGAUGGUUUAGAUGGCAGUAUCACAUGAGAUUUAUUCAUAUUGUGUGUUGGAAUGUAAAUUCUAAUGACCUUUGGAAGCAUUAGUAGUAAAAUUUACUUAGCUGGCUAUUCCUAAGCUUACUAGUGAGUUGGAGUUGCAUGCGUGAAUCAUACCUCUGACCAGUUGUGAUGAUACAAAUUAAGUUGAGUUUAAGGAAGAGACUAAAUUAAUUGCCAUCCUGUCACCACACUGUCCACUUAGCACUGUACAGCUAAGAUCCUUUCAGUUUUUUAAAAAAUACUUUUUUAAUACCACAGAUAUAAGAACCUGCAAUGGGUGCUUUUAAUUUGGGUUUAUGCUGACCUUUAUGUAUCAGAUAAUGUGUCUAAAUCCUGAGCCAGGAUCCUAGUAACCCCAAUUUCUAUCUAAGCAUAGUCUAAAAGCUGUCACUCAGUACUAGAACGUCUUUUGUGGUAUGAAAGGAUAAUGUAUAGGGCCUGGAAGUACACUUACAUAUUUGCUUAUUUGGUUAGGUUGUUAUUUUGUGAAUAGAAUUUAAAUUCACUUUUAGAAGUAAUGUCAUAGUUGUCAGUGGACAUGUAUAUUUCAACUAACUAUAAGGAAGACAGAUGGAAAUGUCCUUUUCUUUUUCGUGUCUGAUAAUGCAUUUGCAUUUGUUGAUCUGAGGUCAGCACUUAAGUUGGACAUCUUCAAAUCUUUUUUUUUUUUUAAUUGAGAUGGAGCCUUGCUGUGUUGCCCCGGCUGGAGUGCAGUGGCAUGAUCUUGGCUCACUGCAACCUCUGCCUCCCAGGUUCAAGCGAUUCUCCUGCCUCAACCUCCCGAGUAGCUGGGAUUACAGGUGCCUGCCACCACCUCUGGCUAGUUUUUGUAUUUUUAGUAGAGACAGGAUUUCUCCACUUGGCCAGGCUGGUCUUGAACUCCUGACCUCAGGUGAUCUGCCCGCCUCAGCCUCGCAAAGUGUUGGGAUUACAGGCCUGAGCCACCAUGCCUGGUUUCAAAUCUUAAUUUAAUGGGUGGAGUUAGUUUUCCAAUCACUAGUAGAAACUCAGUAACCAUAAAUUUUGAAUGCUUGUAUUUUAUUGGAGUCUGGAAUUACCACCUCCAGAGAUAUUUAGAUUGACUUUGUAGUUCUGAUUGGUGGUAUCACUUUUGAUUUUUGAGCAUCUCAAUUAGCUUAUCUUUUCCUAGAAGAAUAUUUUAUCUUCAAUUUUUAUAUAUAGAUGCAAUAUAUAAUUAUAAAUACUAUAUAUAACAUGUACUUGUGAAUCCGCAUUUCAACCAUACAUCAACAUAGAGUAGUUGUAGUUAGGUUCCUUUUUAAAUGUAUUUUAAUUUGAAAUUUACUUGUAUGAAUAAACUCAUUCAUUAAAUUUUUUUCUCAACAUUAUUUAAUAUUGACAUAUUGUCACCAGUGAGUCUGAAAUAAUUCUCAUGCCUUAAAUGUGACUAUUUCAAAGUAUUACUCUUUUUUUUUUUUUUUAAGUAUUUAUUGAUCAUUCUUGGGUGUUUCUCGGAGGGGGGAUUUGGCAGGGUCAUAGGACAAUAGUGGAGGGAAGGUCAGCAGAUAAACAUGUGAACAGGGUCUCUGGUUUUCCUAGGCAGAGGACCCUGCGGCCUUCCGCAGUGUUUGUGUCCCUGGGUACUUGAGAUUAGGGAGUGGUGAUGACUCUUAACCAGCAUGCUGCCUUCAAGCAUCUGUUUAACAAAGCACAUCUUGCUCCGCCCUUAAUCCAUUUAACCCUGAGUGGACACAGCACAUGUUUUAGAGAGCUCGGGGUUGGGGGUAAGGUUAUAGAUUAACAGCAUCCCAAGGCAGAAGAAUUUUUCUUAGUACAGAACAAAAUGGAGUCUCCUAUGUCUGCUUCUUUCUACACAGACACAGUAACAAUCUGAUUUCUCUUUCUUUUCCGCACAUUUCCCCCUUUUUCUAUUCGACAAAACCGCCAUCGUCAUCAUGGCCCGUUCUCAAUGAGCUGUUGGGUACACCUCCCAGACGGGGUGGCGGCCGGGCAGAGGGGCUCCUCACUUCUCAGACGGGGCGGCCGGGCAGAGACGCUCCUCACCUCCCAGACGGGGUGGCGGUCGGGCAGAGACACUCCUCAGUUCCCAGACGGGGUCGCGGCUGGGCAGAGGCGCUCCUCACAUCCCAGACGGGGUGGCGGGGCAGAGGCGCUCCCCACAUCUCAGACGCCGGGCGGCCGGGCAGAGACGCUCCUCACUUCCCAGACGGGCUGGCAGCCGGGAAGAGGCGCUCCUCACUUCCCAGACUGGGCGGCCGGGAAGAGGGGCUCCUCACAUCCCAGACAAUGGGCGGCCAGGCAGAGACGCUCCUCACUUCCCAGAUGGGGUGGCGGCCAGGCAGAGGCUGCAAUCUCGGCACUUUGGGAGGCCAAGGCAGGCGGCUGGGAGGUGGAGGUUGUAGCGAGCCGAGAUCACGCCACUGCACUCCAGCCUGGGCACCAUUGAGCACUGAGUGAGGGAGACUCCGUCUGCAAUCCCGGCACCUCGGGAGGCCGAGGCAGGCAGAUCACUCGCGGUCAGGAGCUGGAGACCAGUCGGGCCAACACGGCGAAACCCCGUCUCCACCGAAAAAAUACAAAAACCAGUCAGGCGUGGCGGCGCGCGCCUGCAAUCCCAGGCACUCCGCAGGCUGAGGCAGGAGAAUCAGGCAGGGAGGUUGCAGUGAGCCGAGAUGGCGGCAGCACAGUCCAGCCUCCGCUCGGCAUCAGAGGGAGACCGUGGAGAGAGAGGGAGAGGGAGAGGGAGAGGGAGACCGGGGAGAGGGCAUCAGAGGGAGACCGUGGAGGGAGAGGGAGACCGGGGAGAGGGAGAGGGAGAAAAGUAUUACUCUUAAGGAUUUGUGUAUGGAGAAGGGUAUUGAGGUUGUGGAAUAGAGGUAGGAUUGGUGUUGGAGGAAGGGUUACUUACCUUAUGGAAUCGGAAAUUUGAGACAGGUUUCUGAGUGAAAAUAGGUAAAUGUGGUAUUGUAAUAUAAUAAGAAAUACAUAUUUGGUCUCUGUUCCUGGUUCCUGGCACACAGCUCUUAAAACCCUUGGACUGACCAAAGUACUGUAAUAAAUGUCUUUUUGUAUGCUAAUGAGAUGACUGGUGGCUGGGGCUCCUGGAUAGCUUCAGGGUGGGGGAGCUGGUUGCUAGGAGAAGCAACCAACCUAUCUCCUGGGAGGGGAAGGGGAAGAGCCUGAAGGAUGAGUUGAUAACCAGUGGCCAGUGAUUUAAUCAGUCAUGUCUACAUAAUGAAGCCUCUAUACAAACCCAAAGGAUAGAGUCUGGAGAGCUUCCAGAUGGAUGAGCAAGAACACAUCCAAGUGCAGCGAUUGGGGGUACAUCCCAGGUACAGGAGAUCAGAAACUCUUGCUCUUAGGACCCUUCCAGACCUUCCCCAUGUGUCUCUUCGUCUGGCUAUUCAUUUGUAUCCUUUAAAAUAUUAGUAUUGGCUGGGCACAGUGGCUCACACCUGUAAUCCCAGCACUUUGGGAGGCCGAGGUGGGUGGAUCACCUGAGGUCAGGAGUUCGAGACCAUCCUUGCCAACAUGGGGAAACCCCGUCUCUACUAAAAAUACAAAAAUUAGCUGUGCAUGGUGGUGGGCGCCUGUAAUCCCAGCUACUUAGGAGGCUGAGGCAGGAGAAUCACUUGAACCCAGUAGGUGGAGGUUGCAGUGAGCCGAGAUUGUGCCAUUGCACUCCAGCCUGGGCGACAGAAUGAGACUCCAUCUCAAAAAAAAAAAAAAAUCUUUCUAAUAAAUGGGUAAACAUAAGUAAAGUGUUUUCCUGAGUUCUGUGAGCUGCUCUAGCAAAUUAAACUCUGGGGAGAGCUUAUGGGAACCCUGAUUUAGAGCUAUUGGGCCAGAAGCACAGGUCACAACCUGGGGCAUGAGAUUGGCAUUAGAAGUUGGGGUGGUCUUCUGGGACUGAUCCCUUAACCUAUGGGAUGUGAUGUUAUUUCCACAUAGUGUCAGAAUUGAGUUAAAUCAUAACUCACUUAGUGUCUGCCAGAGAAUCUGGUGUCAGGAGUGUGUUGUGUGAGAGUAGAAAAAACACUGUUUUUUUCCCCAUCUUUAAUAAUAAAAUAUGCUAUAAGGUGUAGUAGAGCAUUAUCCCUUAUUAGGAAGAGUUUAUAAUUAGUUAUUUUUGUUGUUAUGGCUGAACCAGACCUUUGCUUUGUUCUCAGAAAAUAUCUAGCAAAGUUACACAUUUUCUUUGGUUCAAUAAGUGUUGUUUGUUGAUCUAGUUGUAUAUUUAAAAAUAGUGUUAAAAAUAAAAUAUGUGCUUAUUACACAUAAAAUUGACAAACUGAAAAAGUAGAAGGAACAAGUUAAUCAACAAAUAUUUAUUAUCUUCACAAAUAUUUAUUAUUACCACCAGGCACUGUUCUCUGCCCUGGGGAAAUGGUGUUAAACAAGUCAUGUACCCAGGGGGCUUACAUUCUGGUAGCUGAAUGGAGGAGAAGGAUGUACCAAUAAGUCUGUUAUUCUCAGUAAGUGUGAAAAAGAUAAAAUGUGUAGUGAGAAAAGAUGGGUGGUGAAGGCAAGGCCUAACUUGGUUGGGGUGGUCACGGAAGGCUUCUUAGGGAGGGACGUUUGAGUUGCUCUGAAAGAUGAGGAGGCAGUCAUUGGAGAGCAGGGAAAAGAGUACUCUAAGCAGAAGAGGUCCAAAGGCCUUGCAAUGAAAAUGAGCUUGCUUUGUUCAAGGGACAGAAAGUAGGAAGAAAAUAGUGUCCGUAGCAAAACCAUAGGACACAUACUGAGUCUUUGUAGAUGUAUACUUUGGCUUGUAUUUUUAGAAUUUGUAUUCUGCUGUUUUAAUAUUUGCUUCAUAAUAUAAACAUUCUUCAUUUCAUACCUUAGUAAACAUUUUUAGUGUUGACACAAUUAAUUUUGUAAAUGUAUCGUGGUUGACUUACCCAUUCCCCAAUAGUUUGGCAUUUAGAUCCCUCCUCCCCCCCUUUUUUUUGCAUUAUUGUAAGUAUUACAGUGAGCACUUUGGAUAUAAAACUUUUUUGCUUCUUACGGUUGGUCCUCAGAAGGCAAAAUAUAAACUGGGGCAAAGAUAUGAAUUAUUUAGUAUUUAUUGCCAGAAUAUUUGGCAAAAGCUUUAGUUUAUGUUCCAAUUACCAAAGUGUAGAGAGUGUUUACUGUAUCCUGGCCAGCAUUAAGUAUUAUUUUUGUUUUGAAAAUUUUUUUUGCUGUGGGAAAAUGCAGAUAACAUAAAAUUUACCAUGGUAACCAUUUAAAAGUGUACAAUUCUGUGGCAUUAAAUAAAUCCACAGUGUUGUGCAACCAUUGCCACUAUCUACUUCCAGAACUUUUUCAUCACCCUAAGUGGAAAACCUUGUACCCACCAAGCAAUCAUUUCCCAAUCCCUGUUCCCCAUCAACCCCUGGCAGCCAUGAAUCUGCUUUCUGUCUCCAUGGAUUUGCCUAUUCUGGACAUUCCAUGUAAAUGGAAUUAUAUAGUACAUGGCUUUUUGUGUCUGGCUUCUGUGACUAAGCAUAAAGUUUUCAGGGUUCAUCCGUGUCAUAGCAGUGUCAGUACGUCUUCCCUUUUUAUGGCUAAUAUUCCAUCGUUUGGAUAUACCACAUUUUGAUUAUUUAUUCAUCUCUUGAUGGACAUUGGGUCAUUUCCACCAUUUAGCUCUUGUGAAUAGAGCUGCUAUGAAGAUUUAUGUAUAAGUAUUUGAAUACCUGUUUUCAGUUUUUUCGGACAUAUAUCUAGGAGUGGAAUUGGCCGGGUUACAUGAUAGGUAAUUUUCCAUUUAGCUCAUUGAGGACUGGCCAAACUGGUUUCCCCGUUGGCUGUGUGAUUUCACAUUCUCACCAGCAGUGGAUGAGGGUUUUAAUUUCUCCAUAUCCUCACGAAUACAUUAUUUUUAAAUUUUUUGUGUUUUGUUUUUUAUGAUAGCCAUCCUAGUGAGUGUGAUUUUUGAUUUCAUUGUGGUUUUUUAUUUUCAUUUCCCUAAUGACUAAAAAUGUUCAGCAUCUCUUCAUGUGCUUGUUGGCCGUUGAGUAUUAUCUUUUUCUCACUCUGUCACCUGUGCUGGAGUGCAGUGGUGUGAACACAGCUCACUGCAGCCUUGACCUCCUGGGCUCAGCUGAUCCUCCCACCUCAGCCUCCUGAGUAGCCAGGACCAAAGAUGUGGGCCACCACACCUGGCUAAUUAAAAAAUUUUUUUUUUGUCUGGGCAAGGUAGCUCAUGCCUGUAAUCCCAGCACUUUGGGAGGCUCGAGGCAGGUGGAUCACCCGAGGUCAGUAGUUCAAGACCAGCCUGGCCAACAUAGUGAAACCUCAUCUCUACAAAAUAUAUAAAAAUUAGCUGGGCGUGGUGAUGCACGCUUGUAGUCCCAGCUACUCAGGAGGCUGAGGGAGGAGAAUCACUUGAAUCUGGGAGGCAGAGGUUGCAGUGACCAGAGAUCGCGCCACUGCACCCCAGCCUGGGCAACAGAGCAAGACUCUGUCUCAAUAAAUAAAUAAAUACGUAAAUAAAUAAAUAAAUUUUUUUUUUUGGUAGAGACAAGGUUGCCCAGGCUGGUCUAGAACUCCCAGGCUCAUACAGUCCUUCCACCUUUGGCUCCCAAAGUGCUGGGAUUACAGGGACUAUUAUCUUUUUUCAACUUGAAAUUUUUAUUGAAAUAUAAGAUGUACAGAAAAGGGCACAUAGCACCAACUCAGUACACAUGUGUAACCAUCACUUUAUGCCCUCUUCUAGUCACAGUCUUUCACCAAAGAGUAACCCCACCUGACCCAGAACAGCGUCAAUUAGUUUUGCCUGCUUUUGUACUCAUGUGAAUAGAAUCACAUAGAACAUAUUCUGUAUCUGCCUUUUUCGGCCUAACGUUAGAUCUGUGCCGUUCAUCUGUAUCAUUCAUUUUAUUCUAUUGUGUGAAAUACUAGUUUAUUCAUUCUAAGGUUGAUGGACAUUUGGAUUGGUUGCAGUUUUUGGAUCUUAUAAUGUCGUGAAUAUUCUGCUAUUUGUUUUUUCUUGAGCGUGUAUGUGGGCCAAAUACAGCUUUUGGAGUGGUUGAUCGUACUAGCGUUAAAAUGUCGCCAUUGGUGUAAAUAAUUCCUCUACUUUGUUGGCUGUUUCUUUUUUUUCUUUUAAUUUUAGUUCUGUUUAGGCAUGGAGAAGUUGUAAGUGGUUUUCUUUUGUUCAUUUAUUUGGUUAGUUUUAAGUUUGGAUUGUGACCCCUUCAUCCAGAGUUUUAAAAUUGGAAGUCAGCUCUCUUGAGUCACAUAAUCUUGGUAUGAAGUUUAAGAUGAAUGAAAUGCAAGCAUACUUGGGAAAAAAAAGAAUUUUUUUUACUGGGGACCUAUCGUUCUUUUCUUACCAAAUGUUAAGAGUAUCCCCCAAUAUUUUUAUAGUAAUUAUAAAAUCACAAAUUUAUUAUAACCCCACAGUAGGUCCUAGAGACUAACUGGAACAGAAAGCAAUAUUGUUUUAAUUGUUUGAUCUUUGAGCUCUAGUAAACUUCUCUAUCUUUUCUUAUUUUCUUUUAAAAUUACAAAAUAAUGCGUACAUAUUAUAAAACAUUUGAAAGUUACAUAAGAAAAUCAAAAUAAUGUCACUACUUGAGAGAAAAUCACGUUAGUACAUACACUUCCUGUUUGUUUUUAGGCAAUGCUAGUUUUUUUUUUUUAUUGAACAUAAUGUUCUAUAAUGUGAUUUCCCCUAAAUAUACUGUGAAUACUUUCCUCUGUAAUUAAAUAUUAUUCUAAAGCAUGGUUUUAAAAAAUUAGAGCAUGAUUUAAAAAUUUAAUUUUUAUCAUGUGGUAUACAUGUACAUAUUAAUAAUUUAUAUAGUCAUGUAGUUUUACAAGGCUAAUAAAAAAAGUAGGCCGGGCGCGGUGGCUCAUGCCUGUAAUCCCAGCACUUUGGGAGGCUGAGGCAGGCGGAUCACUUGAGGCCAGGAGUUCAGACCAGCCUGGCCAACAUAGCAAAACGCUGUCUCUACUAAAAAUAUAAAAAAUUAGCUGGGGAUGGUGGCGCAUGCCUGUGCUCCCAGAUACUCAGGAGGCUGGGCAUGAGAACCACUUGAACCUGAGAGGUGGAUGUUGCAGUGAGCCAAGAUCGUGCCACUGCAUUCCAGCCUGGGCGACAGAGAGACUCCAUCUCAAAAAAAAAAAAAAAAAAAAAAAAAAAAUCCAUUUUUCCCUUUCCUGCUAGAAUCCAGCUCUCAAGAGGAACCACUAUCAACUGACAUAUUUCUUUGGUAGUUUUUAAUUUCCAGAUAACGUGUUUAAACUAACCUUUUUUGACUGUUUCAAUUUUAGAUUUAUCUUUUGACUUGCCAUGAUGGAAGAUAGUGGUUUAGCUGUUUUACAUUCUCCUCCCCACGAUGCAUACUUUCCAUCUUCUCUAUAUGGUUAUAUAACCAAUUUUGGUUAAUCAAAGUUUAUAUAACUAUUCACAUUGGAGCCAUGCUGUGUACUAUUUUAAUAUGGUUACUUUUUUUUUUUGAAACAGCUUUUUGUUUUAGCUGGAUUUAAUGAAUCUUUGUGUUUAUUUGUUUUCCAUGCAUUCAUCACUUACUCAGCUCAGACUAUACUACUAAAGUUUAACUCUCCUUUUAAUAUAAUAAACACAUCAGGUAAUCUUUCAGUUUCUUUUUUUUUUAUUUUGGAUACCUCUAACUUUGUGUUCCAGUUGAACUGAUUGCCUUCUUGGCUUGCUUCCUGGAGUGGGAUUUUUACCAUUUUCAUGGGAAUUCUUUCAGCCUUAUUCUGUUGCUUUUCAUUGUAGCUCCCUUAGAAAUAAAGCAUGGGAAGCAAAUUCUUUGAGACUUAGAAUAUUUAAGAAUAUCUAUUAGAGCCUACUCUUGAUAGAUAACUUGGCUGUAUUUACAAGUCAAGGUUGGAAAUUAUUUUUCUUCAAAAUUUUGAAGGCAUUACUCAAGUGACUUGUUUCUAGAGUUGCUCUGAAAAGUCUGAUGUCAUUUUGAUUCCAAGACCCCCCUCCUUUUUUUUUUUUUUUUUUUUUUUUUUGAGACAGAGUCUCGCUCUGUCGCCCAGGAUGGAGUGCAAUGGUGUGAUCUCUGCUCACUGCAACCUCCGCCUCCCGGGUUCAAGCGAUUUUCCUGCCUCAGCCUCCUGAGUGGUUGGGAUUACAGGUGCCUGCCAUCACACCUGGCCAAUUUUUGUAUUGUUAGUAGAGACGGGGUUUCGCCAUGUUGAUGAGGCUGGUCUCGAGCUCCUGACCUCAGGUAAUCUGCCCGCCUCUGCCUUCCAAAGUGCUCAGAUUACAGGCGUGAGCCACGGUGCCUGGCCUCCAAGACCCUUAUAAGAAAGCUGUUUUUUUCUUUCUGGAAACCUUUAGGAUCUUCUCUUAUUCCUGGUGUUCUGAAAUUUUAUAAUGAUAUUUCUUAAUGUGAGUCUUUGUUUAAAAAAAAAAAAAAGUCUGUUGUGCUGUGCCCUUGAUGGAUCUUUUUAUUUUAGAAACAUGCCCUUCAAUGCUUAGAAAGUUGUUUCUUUGGUAAUGGACUCUGAAAAGGGAGAACUCCUUGUUAGGGGGUUUUUGGGUCUUCUGAAUUCUUUUAUCUACUCUUUGCUGUCUGAUUUUGUCUUUUUUUUUUUUUUUUUUCUGUUUUUUAUAUUCCAACUCCUUUAUUGGAUUUAAAGUUUCUGCUGUCUUUAAUUUGAAAAGCUUUUCUUUUGUUUUAUGAAUGUUUCUUUUAAUCAUUCUUAUUUCACGGAUGCGUAUCUUUUUUUCGACCCUUUGAGGAUAUUAUGAUUCUGUUCCUUGCGUUGUUUCUUUUUUUCCCUUGCUCUGUUUUGAUUCCUAUCUUUCAAAUUAAAGGUUUUCUUAAAUGUUUGAUGUUCCUUGCCUAUCUGUUCAGACUUAAGCCUGAGGCUUUUAAAAAAGUUUUUAUUUUUAAAGCAAGUUGGGAAGUCUUUCCAUGGUAUGGGCCUGUGACAUGGUCUUCCUCUCUGAGGGAUGAACUGGUGAAUCUGGCUUUCCGUGGGGACCCUCAGCUGUCAGUGUCUCCAGGUCUCUCUUUUUUAGGCUGUUUUGUUUUCCUGUCUAAGCUUGACUGCCAGAAUUCUGUGGUGAAUUGGGGAAAAGGAGGGUGGUGGGUGGGUGGUAAGUUAUCAUUCAGUAUUUAGGCUUGCAUUUAAUCCCCAUCAUACCUCCCUCAGAAUGCCUUUGUUUACAGUCUCUCCUGUGUAAACUUCCCAGAGUAAUGGGCUGAGUGUCUGAUGGCAUUGUUUGGGUUAUGAUAUCUGGGAUUUCGAUGAAUGGCUCCGUAUCUAGAAUUUCAACCAGGUGUUUUUUUUUUUUUUUUUUGCCCCCCACCCUGCUCUGGAUUCCUGAACUUUUCUAGGCUUUAUUCUUGGUACAUUCCCUCAGUAAUUCUGCUAGACAGUUUCUGUUUUCUUCAGCCUACUAAGUCAGUUACCUCUAAUCCAUCUGCUUUUCGGCUUUCAAAAUUGUGCUUAUAUCUAGAGCAAGCUUGUCCAACCCAUGGCCUGUGGGCCACAUGUGGCCCAGGAUGGCUUUGAAUGUGGCUCAACACAAAUUCGUAAACUUUCUUAAAACAUGAGAUUUUUGUUUUGCGAUUUGUUUUUUUUAAGCUCAUCAGCUGUCGUUGUUGUUAGUGUAUUUUACGUGUGGCCCAAGUCACUUCUUCCAGUGUGGCCCAGGGAAGCCAAAAGAUUGCACACUCCUGAUCUAGAGUCUGCUGUAGUGUCCUCUUCUGUUUGUUUGUAGUCUCUGCAUUUAUAAAUUAUUUAUUAUUUAGUGUUGGACUUGUAAGAAACACUCUGCUCCACUCUGCCGAGGAAAAGGUGAGCUAUUGUGGUGAGGCCUUCACAGGUCUGUGUGCCUGGCACUCUCAGCUGCAUUAUUCAGGACCUUGGGCUGUACGUAGUUAUUUUAUUGGAUUUGUGUGAGAAGGGCUAGUUUUGUGAUUGGUUAAGUUUAUUGAAAAUAAUUUUUUUUUUUUUUUUUUUUUUUUUUUGAGACAGAGUCUUGCACUGUCGUCCAGGAUGGAGUGUAGUGGUGUUAUGUUGGCUCACUGCAAUCCCUGCCUCCUGGGUUCAAGGGAUUCUCCUACCUCAGCCUCUCAAGUAGCUGGGACUACAGGUGCACUCCACCACGUCCAGCUAGUUUCUGCAUUUUUAGUAGAGAUGAGGUUUUGCCAUGUUGACUAAGGCUGGUCUCCUGGCCUCAACUGAUCUGCCUGCCUUGGCCUCCCAAAGUGUUAGAAUUAUAGGCGUGAACCGCUGCAUCUGGCCAAAAGUUGACUUAUUUUGAAUGGACUACAUUAUAGCUUAACUAGAUUGUACGAGUGCUUAUCAACUAAUAUGUUAAAAUAUGGUAAUUCCUUUUUUUUUUUUUUUGAGAUGGAGUCUUGCUCUGUGUUGCCCAGGCUGGAGUGCAGUGGUGCGUUCUCAGCUCACUGCAACCUCUGCCUCCUGGGUUCAAGCAAUUCUGCCUCAGCCUCCCGAGUAGCUGGGAUUACAGGUGCCUGCCACCACGCAUGGCUAAUUUUUAUAUUUUUAGUAGAAAUGGGGUUUUGCUGUGUUGGCCAGGCUGGUCUCGAACUCCUGAACUCAGAUGAUCCACCUGCCUCGGCCUUCCAAAGUGCUGGGAUUACAGGCAUGAGCCACUGCACCUGGCCAAAAUAUGGUAAUUCUAAUAGGUCACAUUCAGGUGUAUUUUUUUUAAUGGUCUAAUAUAACAUUAAAAGUAUUUGUGAAAAAUUCCAUUUUGGUAUUUUAAGCAUAAUCUAUCCAAAAGGAACAUUAAAAAAUAAUAAUAAAAGGGGAAUGUGAGGUUUAGGUUUUUAAGAUGUUCAGUAUUUUUAGGUAAGAGUGUUGUAGUAGUUUGCUAGGGCUGCCAUGACAAAAUACCACAGACCCAGUGGCUUAAACAGUACUUUCCUCACAAUUCUGAAGGCUAGAAGGUCAAGGUGUUGGCAGGGUUGGUUCCUUCUGAAGCCUCUUUCUUGGCUUGCAGAUGGCUCUCCUUCUCUGUCCACAGUGAUCUUCCCUCUGUGUGUGUCUGUCCUAAUCUUCUUAUAAGGGCACCAUUCAUAUUGGAUUAGGGCCCACCUGUAUACUCAGUUUACCUCAGUUACCUCUUUAAGGCCCUGUCUUCAAAUACAGUCACAUUCUGAGGUAAUGGGGGUAAGGAUUUUCACAUGUGAAUUUGGUGGGUGUUGGAGGGGCACAGCUCAGCACAUAACAAAUAUUUUUAUUAUCUCAUGCAUUUAAAGGAGUAUCAUUUCUGAUACACUUCAGAAAGGAAUGUAUUAGUGUGAUGAAGUGGAAAUAACUCGGACAUUGUAGUCAGAUAGGUAGGCCUGGUUUGAACUCUAGCCUUGCCUCUUAAUAGUUCCCUAAAUUUUUGUAACUUCUCUGAGACUUGCUUCCAAAUCUAUGAACUGGGAGUAACUGUACAUCACAGAAUGAUGGUAAGAAAUUAAGGACGAUGUAUGUUAAAAGUGCCUGACAUCGAGUUGACUUCUAAAUAUUAUGUUCUUACUGGUCUUUUCUCUCCCCCACUCCCCAAAGUAGUGUUUUGUAUCCUUCCCCCUUAUUUAAUAUCAGAAGGUGUCAAUUUCGAGUGUAGAUAUGUAUCAUUUUAAAAUUGCUUAGUCUUUCUAUUCACAAGUGGUUGAAUAUCAGCAGUUUCUUAAGAUUCAAUCUACAAUUGUAUUUACCCAGUCGCUUGUCAGAAUUUCCAAUCAUCAUGUAGUUCAGUUUAACAUUUUACAUGCUUUAAGUGAAACCUACAGAAGUGUAAUCUGCUGAGUCAGUGGAUAUUCACGUUUCAAAGGUUCUUGAUGCAUAAGGACAAGAGCCUUUGCUUUUUUAUCAGCAAGGUAUGAGGAUGCCCUUUUCCCACUCUAACAUUACUGUUUUCUCCUAAGUAUCAAAGUCUAAAAGGAUAUCUUGUUUUAUUUAACUUGCAUUUCUUUACUAGCUAGCUUUAAUGUUUUUCAUAUCUUUAUCAGCCCUCUCUAAAUCUUUUAUCAAUUGUCCUUUUUUUGUUUGUUUUUGUUUGAGACAGGGUCUUGCUGUGUUGCCCAGGCUGGAGUGCAAUGGCGCAAUCUCGGCUUACUGCAACCCCUGCCUCAUGGGCUUAAGCGAUUCUCCUGCCUCAGCCUCCCAAGUAGCUGGGACUACAGGCACCCACCACCAUGCCUGGCUAAUUUUUUUUUUUUUUUUUUUUUUGGUAGAGACGGGGUUUUACCAUGUUGGCCAGGCUGGUCUCGAACUCCUGACCUCAAGUGAUCUGCCCGCCUCGGCCUCCUAAAGUGCUGAGAUUACAGGCGUGAGCCACUGCGCCUGGCCACAUUUGUACAAUUUUAAAAUAUUGUUUUUUUCUAGUGGAUAAGGCACACAAUAGUAGUCUCCCUUUGUUUAAUAGCUGUCUGGGGCAUAUUUUCCCACCUAUUUAUUUACCCCCAUUUAUAUUAAGCCCUCAUUUUCCUCCUUUAGCUCUGCCUGCCUGUUCUCCCUCAGCAAGUCAUUGACAUUUUCCAAAGUUAAGAGAAACAGUAAUAACUUCACUGAAUAAAAAUAGUGAGAGAGCCUGGACUUUGAUUAUGUCCAGAAUACCUCCUAAGAGUGUUAUUUUCAAAGUCAAAGUGAUAAGGAAUUUUGGUUUUUAUGUCUGCCACUGAAAGUAGCUUGUUUAAAUUUGAGUUUAAUUAGUAGAAUGACAGUGUUAUUACUCAUAGUGUGUAGUGUUAUUAAAGAUUCUUUGGCAUACAUGCAAGUUUUUGCUUAUUAGAAGUUUCUAGUUGAAAUUAUAGCACUCACAAAAAGUUUUGAAUAAAUAAGAUUUAGAAUGAGUGACCCCUGAAAACCUGGUAUGCAAAAGGCUACUGGGUAAUAAUUUCAUUAAUUUUAUACCACAUGUGUGAUUUCACCAUACUUUUUUUGUUCCUUGUGGUUGAUUCUAAGUGAUCAGCAAUUUUUAUUUUGACCAUUUAAACCCAUAGCCAUUAGCUACUUAAAUUUGUGAAAUUCUUUGUAGUGAUUUCAGUUUUACAAGUUUGUAUCUUGGCUGAUGGUCUAAUUUUGAAAACUUUACAUUUGGUAGAUACCAAUGUUUUUCUUAAUGUACUUUUUCACAGUCCUUCUGAUUGAUUUCAAAGUGUUGUCUUUGAAAAUAAACAUGACUCAUAGCACUUGGGUAGCCAGAGCAUGCCUGUAAUGAAUGCCUCUGUACAUUUUGAGGCUGUGGUAGAAUAAACAUAGCAGUUCCUUUCCUUUUUGAAAUGGAAGUUUGAUACUAGUACUGAAUUUAAAGAUGAACAGAGCUUAGUUUUGGAGAAAGAGAAAAGCACGGUUAUAUUUGCAGGUACACUUUUUUCUAACUUUCAUUGACUAUUUUUGAGUGUUAAUGUGUAAUUAUUAAAUUAAUAAAAGUAAUUUUAUAGAAGCUGCAAAUUACCAUAUUUCAAUUUAUUUCAGGGGUUAUUCUUUUAAUAAUUUAGGAGCUUUAAAGUAUGUAUCUCAAGCGCUAUAUAAUAAAGAGCCAUCGGUGUAGUUAAACUUUUGAGCUUUUAAGAAGUUAUACAUAUAAUUCUAAAUAUUUGCUUAAUUAUUUAUUUUUACUUAGGGAGAAUGACUGCUUAAAGGUUGAGUCUUCACAUUUUGGAUAGCCAAGAACCAUUAACAAAUUUCUAUUGUUUUUGCCAUUGAUUUGUGGGUACCUUUUAAUCCUUUAUUAUCAUUUAGUUCUUUGUGUCCCAGAGUAAGUUCUCAUUUAGUUCUAUUUGGGUAUUUGUUUUUGUGCUCAUAUCUCUUACUGUUGGCUAUACUUCAUAGUAUGUUUUAAUAUCUGGUCAAGCAAGUUUAUUUUUUUUUUUGAGGUUGAUUUAGCUGUUGGUUAGCCUUUAUUUUAGCAUGAACAUUGUAGGCUGUUUAUUGAAUUCUUUAAAGAAUCAAACUGGCAAUUUGAGAUUGCAUUACAUUUAUAGAUUAAUUUUGGUGGAGAAAUGUUAUUCUAUUUGUGGAUUGUUUUGGUUCUUCUAGAUAGAUGAUGAUGUCAUCAGCAGCAGUGACAGUUUUCUCUCUUUCUUUUCAAAUGUUACACUCUUAUUUUUUACAGUGUUGGCCAGUCUGGCACUGUGCUAGACAGCAUGGUCAUAUUUGUUGACAUAGGGAAAGGCUUUUGAAGUCUCUAUUUUAUAUUUGUUAUACGUUUUUGAUAUAUAUAUAUAACCUUUGCUAAAUUAAGGAAACUCCCUUCUAUUCCAGGUUUGCAUAGAUUAAAAAAAUUAUUAAGUAGGUUCUUCUUUUGUCCAGUUGUUUUCCUGCUUCUAUCAAGAUAACCACCUGAGUUUUUUCUUUUAGCCUUUAAUAAUUAACAACAAAAAAACACUGUUGGAUUUGAUUAGUCAGUAUUUUAUUUAGGCUGUAACUUUAUAGCAUUGUUAUCUGGUUUUAGAUUCAAUACUAGCCUGAUAAAAAUGACCGUAGCUUUUGUUCUUUUUAACUUUCUGAAACAACUUGUAUAAGAUAAGAAUAGAAUGUUUCUUAAAAGCUUAGUAGAAUCCACCUAUUAAAAAAAGGUCUCAUCACGGAGUUCGUUUUGUUUUACUUUGUUGGGAGAAGAGCAUUGCCAUUUCAGUUGCUUUAAUCUUUUGAUCUGUUUUUCAACCUGUUUUCUUUCAAUCUAUUCAAAUCCUCUUUAUUUCUUCUGAUAAUUUUGUCAUUUCUCUUCUUUUGGAUCUUCUUUGUCUUUUUCUUGAUGAAUCUUACUAGAAUUUUAUCUAGGCUAUUAAUAUUUACCAAGAAACAGCUUUUGGUUUUGUUAUCUUCUUAAUUGUUCAUUUGGACUAGAUUUUCAUUGAUUUCUGUCCUUUAUUAUUUCUUUCCUUUUUAUUUAUUUGGCUUUUCUUUGUUAGGCUUUUCUUUUUUUUCACCUUCUUAUUUCUGGUAAAUGUUUAAAGCCAUAUAUUUUCCUCAAGUUCUUCCUUGGCUCUAACAUAUAUUUUCUAAAUGUUUCCUGAUUUUUAUUGAUUUCCUUUUUAACGUAAGGGUUAUUAAGUUAUAUUUUUUUUAGUUUCCAAAUUUGAAUAUUUAUAAAAAUUAUUGAUUCCUGAGUUCAUUGUAUUAUAUCAGAACAUAAUCUGUAUGCCCUUGUGCCUACCACAUGGUUUAGUAAUAUAAAUGUUUAGGGUAUGUGAGAAAAAAAAUGUAUCCCCGUCCAUUGGGAUGUAUUUCUUUGACCUAAGGAAGUGUAGGUCAUUGCUUUUAGGACUUUCUUUUUUAAUAUAAGUAUUUUGUAAUUGGAACCUUCUCUUUUUUUUUUUUUUGGCGGGGAGAUGGAGUCUCACUCUGUCACCCAGGCUGGCGUGCAGUGGCGCCAUCUUGGCUCACUGCAAGCCCCGCCUCCCAGGUUCACGCCAUUCUCUUGCCUCAGCCUCCCAAGUAGCUGGGACUACAUGCGUCCGCCACCACACCCGGCUAAUUUUUUGUAUUUUUAGUAGACACGGGGUUUCACUGUUAGCCAGGAUGGUCUCAAUCUCCUGACAUCGUGAUCCGCCCACCUCGGCCUCCCAAACUGCUGGGAUUACAGGCGUGAGCCACCGUGCCUGGCCGUAAUUGGAACCUUCUGUUUGUACUGUUGAGAACUUGAAUUUUUUUGCUUAUAUUUUGUCUGCUUGAUCUAUCAGUAGUCUGAACAGAGUUGAUUAAGAGUAAUUGUUGAUUUUUCUCUGACAGUUCUGUUAAUUGUUGAAUAUAUUUUAAGACCUGUUUGAAGUGGGUAGAUAUAUUUUGCUGUCAUUUUCAUCACUAUAUAGCCUCUUCUUCAUGUAUUUUUAAAUCCCUUUUAAUUUGCUUUUUUUGGGGAAAAAUUUCAGACCUUUAAGAAUGUUGUAAGAAUGUUACAAAGAAAAUUAUUUUGCUCAUCAUAUAGCUUUACCAAUUAAUAUUCUUUCUUUUUCUUUUUUUUAGUCUUUUUUAUUUCCUGGUAAAUGUUUAAAGCUAUAUAUUUUCCUCUUAAAUCUCCCAGGCUGCAGUGCAGUGUUGUGAUCACAGCUUACUGCAGUUUUGAGCCCAAAUGAUCCUCCCACCUCAUUUCCCCCAGUAGCUGGGACUCCGGGCGCACACCACAUGCCUGGCUAAUUUUUUAAUUUUUUUGUAGAAAUAGAGUCUCACCUUGUUGCCCAGGCUGGUCUUGAACCCUUGGGCUCAAGCAAUCCUCCCACCUCAGCUUCUCAAAGUGCUCAGAUCACAGGCAUGAGCUACUAUUCUCAGCCUUCUCUAACUUAAGAAGGAAGCUCACUUAGGUCGUUGCUUUUAGGCCUUUGUAUUAGGUUGGUGGAAAAGUAAUUGCGUUUUUUGCCAUUAAAUGUGGCAAAACCACAAUUACUUCUGCACCAACCUAACAUAAGGAUUUAAAACUAUAAAUUUCCCAUUAAACAUUACUUUAGCUGCAUCUAUUUUUUUUCUUAUUUAUUAUUAUUUUUUAGACAGAGUCUGACUGUUGCCCAGGCUGGAGUGCAAUGGCACCAACAUGGCUCACUGCAACCUUGACCUCCUGGGCUCAAGUGAUCCUCCCGGCCUCCGUCUCCCGAAUAGCGGUCUUACUCAUUUUCUACGUGUGUGUUGAGUGCACCAUUUGAGAUGAACAGAGUAUCUGUCAGGCAAGAGCUGCUGUGAUGGUUUAUGAUGAUGCCAAUAAGAAGUGGGUGCCAGCUGGUGGCUCAACUGGAUUCAGCAGAGUUCAUAUCUAUCACCAUACAGGCAACAACACAUUCAGAGUGGUGGGCAGGAAGAUUCAGGACCAUCAGGUCGUGAUAAACUGUGCCAUUCCUAAAGGGUUGAAGUACAAUCAAGCUACACAGACCUUCCACCAGUGGCGAGAUGCUAGACAGGUGUAUGGUCUCAACUUUGGCAGCAAAGAGGAUGCCAAUGUCUUCGCAAGUGCCAUGAUGCAUGCCUUAGAAGUGUUAAAUUCACAGGAAACAGGGCCAACAUUGCCUAGACAAAACUCACAACUACCUGCUCAAGUUCAAAAUGGCCCAUCCCAAGAAGAAUUGGAAAUUCAAAGAAGACAACUACAAGAACAGCAACGGCAAAAGGAGCUGGAGCGGGAAAGGCUGGAGCGAGAAAGAAUGGAAAGAGAAAGGUUGGAGAGAGAGAGGUUAGAAAGGGAAAGGCUGGAGAGGGAGCGACUGGAACAAGAACAGCUGGAGAGAGAGAGACAAGAACGGGAACGGCAGGAACGCCUGGAGCGGCAGGAACGCCUGGAGCGGCAGGAACGCCUGGAGCGGCAGGAACGCCUGGAUCGGGAGAGGCAAGAAAGACAAGAACGAGAGAGGCUGGAGAGACUGGAACGGGAGAGGCAAGAAAGGGAGCGACAAGAGCAGUUAGAAAGGGAACAGCUGGAAUGGGAGAGAGAGCGCAGAAUAUCAAGUGCUGCUCCAUCUUCAGACAGCUCCCUGUAUAACGCUCCACUUCCUGAGUAUUCCAGUUGCCAGCCUCCUUCAGCACCUCCUCCAUCAUACGCUAAAGUCAUCUCAGCUCCAGUGUCAGAUGCCACUCCUGAUUAUGCUGUAGUGACUGCUUUGCCACCUACUUCCACACCCCCUACACCACCACUGCGACACUCAGCGACACGUUUUGCAACAUCUUUAGGUUCAGCCUUCCACCCUGUUCUUCCCCAUUACGCUACAGUUCCUCGUCCUCUGAACAAAAACUCUCGACCUUCUUCUCCUGUGAACACACCCUCUUCUCAGCCUCCAGCUACGAAGCCCUGUGCCUGGUCUACUUCCAAUUUUUCGCCCCUCCCUCCAUCUCCUCCAAUAAUGAUUAGCAGCCCCCCAGGCAAAGCUACUGGUCCAAGGCCUGUCCUCCCUGUUUGUGUUUCUUCUCCUGUGCCCCAAAUGCCUCCAUCACCGACAGCACCCAAUGGGCUGGUUGACUCUGUAACAUAUCCAGUGUCUCCACCGCCUACCUCAGGGCCAGCAGCUCCUCCGCCGCCGCCUCCACUGCCUUCCCUCGCAUCACUCUCACACUGUGGAUCUCAAGCUUCUCCUCCUCCAAGCACCCCUAUUGCCUCAACUCCCUCAUCCAAGCCUAGUGUUCUCCCUUCUCCCUCUGCAGCUGCCCCUGCCUCUGUUGAGACUCCUCUAAACUCUGUGCUGGGAGACUCUUCUGCUUCUGAGCCAGGCUUGCAGGCAGCCUCUCAGCCGGCCGAGACUCCAUCCCAACAGGGCAUUGUCUUGGGACCACUUGCACCUCCACCUCCUCCACCACUCCCACCAGGGCCUGCACAGGCUUCAGUAGCCCUCCCUCCUCCCCCAGGGCCCCCUCCACCUCCUCCACUCCCAUCCACCGGGCCUCCACCGCCCCCUCCUCCCCCUCCUCUCCCUAAUCAAGUACCCCCUCCUCCUCCACCACCUCCUGCCCCACCCCUCCCUGCAUCUGGAUUCUUUUUGGCAUCCAUGUCAGAAGACAAUCGCCCUUUAACUGGACUUGCAGCUGCAAUUGCCGGAGCAAAACUUAGGAAAGUGUCACGGAUGGAGGAUACCUCUUUCCCAAGUGGAGGGAAUGCUAUUGGUGUGAACUCCGCCUCAUCUAAAACAGAUACAGGCCGUGGAAAUGGACCCCUUCCUUUAGGGGGUAGUGGUUUAAUGGAAGAAAUGAGUGCCCUGCUGGCCAGGAGGAGAAGAAUUGCUGAAAAGGGAUCAACAAUAGAAACAGAACAAAAAGAGGACAAAGGUGAAGAUUCAGAGCCUGUAACUUCUAAGGCCUCUUCAACAAGUACACCUGAACCAACAAGAAAACCUUGGGAAAGAACAAAUACAAUGAAUGGCAGCAAGUCACCUGUUAUCUCCAGACGGGAUUCUCCAAGGAAAAAUCAGAUUGUUUUUGACAACAGGUCCUAUGAUUCAUUACACAGACCAAAAUCCACACCCUUAUCACAGCCCAGUGCCAAUGGAGUCCAGACGGAAGGACUUGACUAUGACAGGCUGAAGCAGGACAUUUUAGAUGAAAUGAGAAAAGAAUUAACAAAGCUAAAAGAAGAGCUCAUUGAUGCAAUCAGGCAGGAACUGAGCAAGUCAAAUACUGCAUAGAGGAACAGACUAAGGAGAGAUAGGACUUUAAUCUGGAGGAAAAAUAUCCUACAAACAACAACUGUUCACAACAGCAAACCCCUACAUUUAUGAGCUGUAAGAAGAAAAUGGAGACAAACAGAAGGAGGGAAAAACCAACCUACUCUGAAAGCCUUCAGACAUUAUGACUCUGGUGAUAAGCUCUUUCCCUCUCCGUUUGCUGCUUUUUUCUGGCCUUUACAACAGAAUGGAAGAGAAUCAUUUAAGAGUUCCUGUAACAGUUAUGCAGAAAAUACUAAAACCCAUCAGGCAAGAUCACCACGCAUUGAAAUAUUUUCAUAUCAAGAUAAAGUCGCACAUUUUCCACAAUACAUUGCUAAAAUAAAGAGGAGAAAGGCUUAGGAAGUUUUUUUGCAGAGAGUGCUGGUAAAGAAUUGAGCAAGUUUGCUAUUGUAUUGUAAUGUUUCUCUCAGGUUUGUUCUUCCUAUCAUGUUUGAUAUUCCAUGAAUAAUUGAGAUCAGCCCUAUGUAAGUUAAGAUCAUAAUAUGUGGAACAAAUGGAAUUGUAAGUGCUUUCAAAGGGUAAUAUUUAUAAGAAAGUGUCCGAAAAAUGUUUCUUCAGCUUGAGAAAUUUUAGAAUGAUAGGAAGUUUCUCGAGUUAGCCUUCAUGCAAUUUUGUAGAUUAAAACAUAAAAUUUGUCCAGAACUUAAAGAUUUAGAUGCCUUCCUAAAUUGUUACAAUGCUUUACCAAAUCUAUGACUUCUACAUAACACAAACCAGUGGUCAAAUGUAAACACUAUAUUGUAGAUUUACUGUAGGUUUUCAACCUUUUUUAGAUUUAUGCAUGUGGACAUUUUUAUAAUGUAAUUACAAUCACCACAAGGUUAGCUUUUUUAAUUGCAGACAGUAAUGCAUGUCACACUAAUAUGUAGUGGCCUUUUCAAGGCCUAGUCCCAGGGAAAACAUUUUGUAGAGUAUAGGGGAGUGGGAGGAAGGGGAGGAAUAAUUUUUUAUUUAAAGUUGAUUUCUGCACUAUCUUUUUCUCAGUUACCUGCAUGAAUAAAUAAUGAGAAAUAUUUUGUGACUUUAAUUGGUAAAUAUGUUACAAAACCAAGUACUUAAUCUUUUACAUCAUGUCUUCAGCUAUUUGUAUUUUAACCAGUAAUUUCAAUGGUCUGAAACAUGAUUCUGAGCUUCACAUAAUAUCUUAACUGUGGAACUCAAAAGUUUGAUCACUGAAUUUGGCAGUUAUUAUUACCUAGGUACCCCCGCUGUUACACAGGUGUUUAGAUACGUGUUCCUGAAUGAAGCUGCUUUUGAAUUUUGUUAUGUUGAAAUGCAAGAAAUAACAAUGAUGGCAGCAAUUAAGGUCACAGAAAUCAUUAGGUAAAGGAAAACCAAUGAGGAGUUCUGCAGUUUUCUUUUAAUAAGUAAAGUGAGACUUGGGUGGUGGGAAGAAGGAAGGUGGGAAGAAGGAAUUAGACACUCUGCCUGCCACUCUGCGUGUGUGUGCUCUCGCGCACGUGCUGUCUAUAUGGAAGCCACUCCCUUUUCUUUCCUUUGAAACUGGUAAGGUUAAAAUAGGGGAGAAAUCCUACAUGUUGGAAUGAUAGCUUUUUGGAAAAUUUAAGAAACUCUCCAGGCUCUCCAUCUUGAUUUAUGCUUGAGUUGUUAUGUGCCAUAUUUGCUUUGAACUCUGAUUAUCAGAAGUUUUACUAAAACUUUGAAAUAAUUCACUUUCAUCUGCUUUCUAGAUUUUGUACAUCUCAGUCCAUAAAGCAAAGCUUGUUGAUAGUGUAGUUUUCUAAACGCUGCAAAUUUGCAGCCUUUACCACUACAAAGAAGUUUGGAUGAGGGAUUUUUUUUUUCUUUGUCAAAAUAGUUCCUGUUUCUGUAGAAAUUUCAUUUUUAGAUUAAACUGUGAUGGAUGAGCUAUCAUAAUUCAAGUAUACAUUUCUUUUUUCUAUCAGAUAUUCAUUGUCAUGCAGUAGUAGUAAAAACAUCAAAGAUGCAGCAAGCUUAUUAAGUAUUAUUUUCUAAAAGAAAUAGGAGGCAUUUUCAUCUUUAUUAUUGUACUUUUGGUUAUGCAAACACUUUGAUAAUAUAAACAGUUAUGUCCCCUAUAAAUCUGGUCAGCAACCUCUUUUGAUUUUGUUGGGUAAGUUAAAUAGUCUGUAGUAGGUAGAGUACUGGGUACAAGUGGUCCAAACUAAGAUAAGAGACUAAAAUAAAAUGCUAAAUCUUAAAAGAAACUGGGUUUAUGCACUAAACGUUUUGUGCCUUGGUCUAAUAUUAACAUGAUGUAUGUGUAAACUGACAAAAAAAAAAAAAAAAAAAAACCAGUGUUGAAUCAUGCUAUAUUUCCCAUCAUCCCAGAUUGCUAAAUGUUCUUUCCAAGAAGUCUGAAUGAAUUAUUAUAUACAUUUGCUAUCAUACAUGACAGUUGUGUCAUUAUUAGAGAUUUCAGUAAUUAAAAUGGGAAACAGAAGCCUAAGUUAUUUACCUUAUCAAAACCACGUUCCUUGGAACCACAUUAUUAUGAUGGUUUUUGUGCUCUUGUACGUUGGAUGUCUUAAGCUGAGUACAGUUUAGGGGAUCCUUUCUAAUGACAGGAAGGCACUGCUUUCCUCAACACUGUGAUCUGACCUGUGACAAGUCUGUACUAUCCACUAUGUAAAUGGCUCACAAGUCAAUUGCAAACAAACUGAAUGUACAAAUCUUAGUGCUGGUGCUGAAAUCUCUUCAGAAUAGUCAUCAUGAUUUAAAAGUUUGUUUAAAAAUUUGCAAGCAUCAAGUGUCAAUCAAAACUGAAGAUGAAACACUAAUGAAUGUUGAAUUCUCAUGCUUUUAGGUGUACUUCCUUUUUAGAAUUUUCAGUUUUCUGCUAUUUUUACCGUAACUAUUUCGUUUAAAUUUGUUUCAUUUAAGUUUCCUACACGCUAACUUCGUUUGUGCGAUUGAAAUAAAAUUGCAGUAUAUAUAUGUUGCUUGUUUGUGACACUUAGAUAAUCUUCUGAAAUAAUUUGUUUUAAAGUAAGUUAUAUUGGAUGUGAAAAACACCUUUUAAAGUCCAAGACUUUACUACUUAAAAGUUUACAUGUCACGUCACUAUUCUUUACAGAUUUCAUAGAAGUCGUGAAUACUAAGUAAUGUAUACAAAAGAAAUAUGUGAUGAUGUGUCUACUUUUUGUUUGAAAUAACUGUUGGGUGUUCCCUCUUCUUAUUUUCUCUCUGCCCACCUUGACACAGUAACUUCCUCUUAUAGUCAAGAUGAUGAUUAAGUGUUUAAUUUUUAUUCCAUUUUGUUCUGCAACACGUUCAGGUACUUAAAACUCAUUCAUGCAGUUAGAAUUAUCCUUUAUGUAGUUUGCAUGGUAAAGGACAUUGUGUGGUAAAGGGCAUUAUUGAGUAAUGAAUUUUAAGUAUAGCAAAAUAUGUAUAGUGUUUAUACAUGAUGCUGAUUUCUUAAAACCUACAUAUAAGCAGUAGUACUUUUUCUCUAUUAUAAAGUAUUAAUUUUGAGUUCCAUUUUAUAAUUCUGAUGUCUUCAUUAGAAAUACAAAAAUACAAUCCUUGUAUUUUUUCUUUGACCAGACCCAAAUUUUCCCCUUCCCCCCUCCAUUCUCCUCUCCACUUCUCGUGGACCGCGUGUUCCCAAUAUUCAUUAACAUUUGCAGCCAUUACAGAGUUACAGUUGUAAAAUUUUCAGCUGUUUUUUUUUUUUUUUUUUUGCUCUAGCCUGUCUCAUGUUCUUGCUUCUCUUCAUAUGUAAGUCAGUAUUUUUGUCUACAAAUUAAAAGUCACUUGUCAUUCAAAAAUGAGUUAAGUAACAUGAUAAUCUUUUAAAUUUACCUAGCUACAACUUUUAUGUCUCUUGUAAAUUUAUAUAUACUUUCAGUGCCAUUGUGAAGAAUUGGCCUUUUAAUUCUAAGUAGUAUUACCCUAUGAAGCACAGUGUGCAAAGGUAUGCUACAAGGUCUCUUUAAUUCCUGUGUGGCCAUUAUAAUUUUAUAACACCAUUACCCUUUAAAUUCUACCGAUUAUAAGCAGCGUAAAAGUAACUAUAUAAAGCAAACAUCGCAAAGGAACUCUGCAGGAGCUCUUAAUUCCUUUAUGUAGCUAUCAUAAAAUUCACUUUCCUGAAGACAUUUACUCUCAUUCACUUCCAAACUCCAAACCUUUUUCUGGUAGCACCACUUUUGUUUUUAAUAGAAAGAUGAGUUCAUAUCUGUACAUCUCUCCAAAGCUCUAAGGAAUGAGAAAAGGAUCCUAGUAUAUUGAAAUUACUGAUGUUUAAUACCUCUGCCUUUUCACUAAAAGCCAUUUAAUAUUUUUAAAGUCAAAACUUGACAUACAGGUAUUUAUAAGGAAUCUCCAUGACUCUGAAGGAAUGAAAUUGAUGUAGGUAGCUUUGGCUAUGUAAAGACAUAGUAGAGGACAAUUACUUAAAGAAGAGUUUUCUUUUGAGGAUUUGUAGAUUUGACUAAGCAGCUGAAGUCAGUAACCCCUCAAGAAAGUCCGUUUAUAGAAGCCAAGAACUGUUGGAGGUCUGUGAUGCAGGUUUUUCUGUUCCCAACAUCAAAAGCUGUGGAUUAUUUGGUGUGUUCCCCUUUAUGUUAUCUCUCGAUAAUUUUUGAGACAUCAAGAUUUUUUAAAAUAUCAAUACUGGAAAGAUGAAACCUUCAAAUUAAAACCUAAAAUUGAUUAGAAAGAAAAGUAAAAUAUUAAUGCAGUAAAUUUAGGAUGGUUACAGAUACUCACCAUCAACAUAAAUAAAUGGAGUUCUAGGAUAAAUUAUUUGUGGAAUACUAAUGGUCAAGUCACAUAAGAGUAAAAUCUUUUGGUGAGGAGACACAUUUGACAACUGCUAAAGAAUUAACUAAAUUUGUCUUUCUAAAUAGUUUUCUUUAUAAAGUAACAGAAACAUUGUAAAAGGAUAAAUGACUGUCAUAAUGACUUAGGAUGUUGUAAGAAUGUCUGCCACAUUUAUUGGUUAUUUCUGUUGAAAUCUGAAGGAAUCGAUACAUCUGAAAAUUGAGAAAGGGAAAUAGGACUGUCCCCGUUACAGAUACUCUGUGAUGCACACAACCUUCUAAACGGAAGUGUUAGUAUCAUUUAAAGCACAUAGUAGGCCUUGAGUAUUUGCAGAUUAACAUGCAGAAAAAAUCAAAGAUGAAGCCCCAAUUAAGUGUUUGAACCAAAGAAUCACAGUCACUGAGCUGCACCCCCGUUCUGUGAAGCAUGUUAAAUACUCAUAAAGAGCAGAGAGCAGGGCCCGUAGACGCUUCUGGUGUAGGACACAGGAAUUCUAGGCAGAGGGAGAAAAUUAGGGGCCCCAGUUGGUGGCUGAGAGUAAAAAGAAUAUACCAUUUGAGUAGUGCUGUUCUUUUUCCUCAGUUUUUAAAGACAUAUAAUUCCUAGUAGUUAGGACAUCUAAAUAGCUCGGUAAACUGGUCAGAGGCGGGAGGAUUGCUUGAGGCCAGAAGUUUUGAGAUCAGCCUGGGUAACAGGGAGACUCAUUUCUACAAAAAAAUUUAAAAAUUUAGGCCAGGCAUGGUGGUGCACACCUGUAAUCCCAGCUACUCAGGAGACUGAAGCGGGAGGAUCACCUGAGCCCAGGGAGGACGCGGCUGCAGUGAGCCGUUAUCAUGCCACUGUACUCCAGCCUGGGUGACAGAGCGAGAACCUGUCUCUAAAAAAAAAAAAAAAAAAUUCUAAGAGAAUAUAGCUUUUCAUAGAAAUUAUUAGAAAAGCUUACAUAUUUCAUUAGAGAGCCCAGUUUGUUAGACUACAUUUAUUCCGUAAAAGUUCUAUAUACAAAUGACAACCCAUAGUUUAUCAUGUAAAUCUGAUUUAACUGUUCCCUUCAAUUCCAAGAAAGAUUUCUUCAGCAGUAGAUGACAAUUCUAAAAGCAUAAAGAAAUAACUAAUAAAGGAGAUGGAUGAUGUUAUAGGUUGGUUUGGUUGGGUUUUAGUAAAUAGUUAUUCUUCUAAGAAGGCUUAGAAAAUCGAGAAUUGAAUAGUUGGUACUUUGAAUUCCAUAGGAAAAAGCACUCAGAAGAAAAAGUCUACAUUGGCUAGUGUUUAGAUUGAGAGUUAAUUUUCCCAUCAAGUCCAAAAGUUUCCAUCCAAGUCUAUAGAAACUGAGAGAAAAGGUUCUUGGCUUACACUUAAAAUACACAUUGUUGCAACCAUAUAAGAGAGAUACAUUACAGAACGCUUUUAAAAAUUUGGUCUCUUAAGCGCCUAACAGUCCAUGCUUUAGUCACAUCUGUGAAACCUCUUUUCUUUUUUUCUUUUUCUUUUAUUUUUUUUUUUAAAGAUUAAAGGCAUUUUAAAAAUAAAUGUUUCAUGGCCGGGCAUGGUGGCUCACGCCUGUAAUCCCAGCACUUUGGGAGGCUGAGGUGGGCAGAUCACCUGAGGUCAGGAGUUUGAGACCAGCCUGGCCAACAUGAUGAAACCCCAUCUCUACUAAAAAUACAAAAAAAUUGGCUGGGCAUAGUGGUGGGCACCUGUAAUCCCAGCUCUUCGGGAGGCUGAGACAGAAGAGUCGCUUGAAUCCAGGAGGUGGAGGUUGCAGUGAGCUAAGACCGCGCCACUGUACUCCAGCCUGGGCGACAGAGCGAGAUUCCAUCUCUAAAUAAAUAAAUGUUUUUCAACGUGUUUUAUGUGAGAAAUACCAGCUUUUCAUUAUUACUACCAGUUGAUCUCAGGUGUCACUUGGUUGGUUCUGCUGACCGAGGCACUGGGCAUUUUAAAUAUGGAGUUUCCCUCCACCCAUUGAUCAAGUCUGAGGUUUGUCCAUCCUUGGUGGCAGGCUAGCUUAACCAUGGAUUCACAAACCCCAUUUGAUUGUCGUAAGUCAUAAGGCCACCCCAGUGCCAGUGGUUGGGCAUCACAGUGAGUCUGAGGUGAUGAAUUUGAGUUAGCUGUAGGCUAGUUCCGCAACUCAGCAAUAGCCCAUGGAUGGUUGGUAAAAGACGUUGACUUUGCCACUUAAAUUUCCAGGAGAAGAAUAGCUUAUAGUUUAUCUGAGGAAAGUAAUUGGGAAGGCUUAGAUAUUGAGAAGAAAGCCCUGUUAAAAUCUAGGUAGCAUUUCCUUUCUUCUUUAUUACUAGAGGGAUGGGAGGUUCAGGCCUGAGUCAGGACUUUACAAUUUGGUGUCCUUCCCAGAGGUACUUUGGGCUUGAUCAUUUUAAGUUUCAAUUGCAAAAAAAAAUUUUUGACGGAGUGUUGCUCUGUCACUCAGGUUGGAGUGCAGUGGUGCGAUCUCGGCUCACUGCAACUUCCCCCCCCUGGGUUCAAAGGGAUUUUCCUGCCUCAGCCUCCCAAGUAGCUGGGACUACAGGCGCGUGCCACCAUGCCCGACUAAUUUUUGUAUUUUUAGUAGAGAUGGGGUUUCACCAUGUUGCCCAGGCUGGUCUUGAACUCCUGAGCUCAGGUGAUCUGCCCGCCUCGGCCUUCAAUUGCAGAAGUUUUUGAAGGGAGAAUAUUUGAUCCUCACAUAAAAUGUCCUUGUUUCUGAAAGAAAACAUGGUAAAAAUUGUUAUUGAGUCCAUGUCUUUGCCACCUUGUUGGACUUGAUUUCCCUUUCUCUGUGUUCCUCCCGCCCUCAGUCUCUCUCAGUCUGUCCUUUUUUGUGUGUGGAGUUGUGGGCAGGUCAUUGGACUGGGACUGACUUUACCAGUUUUCAGGCUGUGGGGCUAGUCAGUCAUUCUCUCUGAGCCUUCUACCUCUAAAGUUGAGUUCUUUUUUUAAAUUCUUUUUGUUUUGUUUUUAUUUUUUCCUUGCCACUAUACAAGCAAGGAUAGAUAAAGCUUUUUAUUAUUAUUGUUAUUAUUAUUAUUUCGAGACAGUCUCGCUCUGUCAUCCAGGCUGGAGUGCAGUGGUGUGAUUUCAGCUCACUGCAACCUCUGCCUCCCGGGUUCAAGCGAUUCUCCUACCUCAGCCUCCUUAGUAGCUGGGACUACAGGCAUGCGCCACCACACCCGGCUAAUUUUUGUAUUUUUAGUAGAGACAGGGUUUCACCGUAUUGGCCAGGCUGGUCUCGAACUCCUGACCUCAGGUGAUCCACCCACCUUGGCCUCCCAAAGUGUUGGGAUUACAGGCAUAAGCGACCGUGCCCAUCCCCGAUAAAGUUGAGUUCUGAAUUUCCUCUUUCACUGUAUUCUCGGCAGCUACUGGUUGGUUUAUUCUUUUUUUUUAAUCUUUUUUGGUUUAUUCUUCUUUUGAUCUUUGAAGAGAAGGAGAAAAAAGAUCUGAGUUUGGCUCUCCCAUCUUAAGUGCAGCUUUUAGUUGUUUUAUAGUCAUAGACGCUAUUGCACUGGACAGCAUGCAUCCUGGAUGUAAACAAUGCGGAAAAAUCAAUGGAGUGACCAUCUUGGGGUCAGUGGUGUUGCAUAAAGCACCAGUGGUGUGCUGUUCUGUGUCAGUUUCCUCUGCGCCACGUGCUUUCACAGUUUGAAUUACCAGCAUCUCUGUGGUGGCUUCAGUACAUUCUCCAUUGUGCUUCAACCUGGAAGCACAUUCUGCCGUUCAGAAAGACUGAUUCCAAUCAUGUAAUGGGACCACACGAGAUCCAUGCUCCAAUUAUAUGAAUAGCAGAAGGUCCAUUUGACUCUUGUAGUUCAAGAGCUGUUUCUAAGUAAACAGACUUUCCAGAGCUCGAUGAAGUGAAGAAGCCCUUCUUUCAAUUCCUGGGCAGAAUUCAGUGGUUUUCAUAUCAUCUGAACCUGCUGUGCUGCUGUUUAUUCUAUCACUGUCAGCCUUGAAAGGAAAAAAGGAAUAAUCUUACCCUCCUGCCCUUCUUAUUUUAUAUCUUCCAUCUUAUCCAUCUAUAUCCAUGUAGUCAUUCCUUCCGAGUUCCCUGGUUUUAAUCCAAAAGACUCUGUUUAACAGCAAUGUCUUGGCAGACCAGGUGCCGCUUCCGUGCCAUUUGAGGGCUCUGAGUCUUUGCUUCGUCUUAGGAAGAUAAAGAUAAUUUGGCAGAAAGUCAGAGAUGGAAAUAGCAGUUUGGGAUGAUAAAAGAUGGGUCCUGUUUUGCUGACAUUCUUUUACUUUGGUUCUUGGUGCGUGUCCUUUGGGAUUCAUUUCUUGCUAGCAUGAAUAGGACAUGCUUUUCGUUAGGUGCUUUUCUUUUUUGGAGAACAUGAAGUGUUUCUAACAAAACUGAAUGAGCUAGAAAGAAUUCUAUUUUGAGACAUCUGUAGUUGAUGCAAAGUAUUUCUGUAAUCCUCAAUGACAGUACUUACAUAUUUGCAUAGAAUUUUUUUUUUAAUUUUUGAGGAAACCUCUCUGGAGUCUGUAUUUAUAGGAGCAUCCUGAAAGUCCCUAUUAUGUAGCUGGUGGGAGCGAGAGAGGGACAGCCACACUCGUGCUGUGAGCAGAGCACAACUUCAGGCAGAGUGAAUGCCUUCUGAGUUCUCAUUGGAAGCUUUCUGUUGCUCAGCCUCUGGCAGAUUUCAGAACCUUCUACUUAAGCCAGGUGUGGUGGUGCGUGCUCCUAGGCACAGCGACUCGGGGGGCUGAGGCAGAAGGAUCACUUGAGCCCAAAGUUGGAGGCCAGCCUGGGCAACAUAGCGAGGCCUGUCUCCUUAAAAAAUAAAUAAAUAAAUAAUAAAUAAAUAAAUAAAUAAAAACCUUGUCCUUGACUAUUGUGCUGUCUGCUGCCCCUUUGUAGGGAUGGGGUUGGGGUCAGAAUAAGCAUGUGCAUGAAUGGCGGAAAGCUUUGGUGGUGUUUGUUUGUUUGUUUGUUUUUUGAGAGGUGGGGGAGUCAGCAGUGAACCUUUCUGGUUAAAGAACAACGUACAUAAUUUCUAUUAUGAGAUUUAGAAGGUUAAAUACUUUUUUUUUUCAGGCCUACCAAGUUGAUAGACCAAAAGUAUAUAGUAGAACAGCACAGUAGAAAAAAUUUAAAAGUGAAUUUCUUAUGGUCCAAAAGGAUGGAUAGUCACAGUCCAUAACCUUUCAUAAUAUAUGCUGGAAUUGGAAUCUCUUGUCAUCUUGCUUUGCUCUGAAUUUUAGAACUAGAAGUGUGCAUGUAUGUCAAAAGAUUAUGCAGAGCUAUUUUCUUUGCUAACAAUGUAAACAUUUGCACCCCAUGAAUGGGACUUUAUAAUCUGGAAGUGAGCCUAAGGUUGCGUAUACUGAAGUCAUGUUUUAAAAGUUAAGGUUGACUUAAACAUAUACAAGGCUGUAUUUUAAUUGUAACUAGAAAUCAUUUACUAUGCAUACAGAACCUCAUGUAUCUUAUCAUGGAAUUUGUGAAUUAAUGGGCCUUGCCGAAUUCAAGGGUAAGGGAAACUGGUAACAACUUGUUUUAAAUCAACAUACUAUAAGCUCCUGCUUGCUUGACUCAAGUUGUUUGAAAAUCUGAAUUAAACAGGAUCUCAUUGUCAGGAAACAUCUUCUAAGCUUGACAUCUACGUUUAAGAAGGGAACGUGGAAGAGAAGGUGAGACAUGAAACUAAAACAGCUGGGAGGGUAGGAUCAGACUGCACCUGAUUUUUGGACCAAAGUUUCAUAUAGGAAUAAAUAAAAAGGAGGACCACUUGUGAGCCAACCUAGGAAGGACUUGCCAGAAAGUAGCAGCUCCUGCUGCAAAAUACAGUGCCUUCAAAAUGAUUCUCUGUGUGAAUUGCAUGCAAUUUCAUGUAACCAUAAAGUGUAACCUGUAUGUGCAUGACAUGUGUCUAGAAUGUGUAAAGUUAGGAUUCAGCAGGAAGGGGCCUGGCCCUGUCACUGUGGUGGAUCAGUGGACCUGCUGAAGUCACUGGACUCAUGUGACUUAGGUUUGCAGCAUCAGACCCCUGUGUUUGCAUUAAGUGGCCACAUCGUUGAAAUCGGAUCAAUCUCUCCCUCAGCUUUCUUUCCUACUUUGCAGCUUUGCUGGUUUUAACUGCUUCAUUCUUCUGCUUCUUGGUAUCCUUUUUUCUUUUGAAAUAAAAACAUGAAAUACUUAAUUCAAA